AGUUGACCUAGUGGCUGAAGCACCGCCCAGGAGGAAAAACCGGCGGGGGAAGCAGGGCCGCCUGCACCUACCAAGAUGGUGGCCGUGUUCAGGCCGGGCAGCUUGUCCAGGGGCCUCAACACCGACAUCACAGCCGCAGGACCAACCGUUGCUCCUGCGGUGCGCGCCGAUCUUUCAAACCGCCCUGAGUCCAGCCCCUAGAGCGCGGCCUGGGGGCACGUGCCUCCUUAUAGGCGGGGCUUCGCGGGACGGGACGGGGCCUCUUAAAGGAACCGAACCUUUAUCUCCUUUUCUGAGGGGCGUUCCAGCGCUACCCGUGGAACACGUGGUGGACAGGCCUUUGGUUCCACGCUCCACAGUAAGCAGGUUUUUAGUGAUUCCUUUGUUCACUUUCAUUCAUUCAUGCUCAUACACAGUACUUUUUUUUUUUUUUUUUGAGACAGAGUCUCGCUUUGUGGCCCAGGCUGGAGUGCAAUGCGCGCAAUCUCGGCUCACUGCAACUUCUGCCUCCCGAGUUUAAGCGAUUCUCCUGCCUCAGCCUCCCAAGGAGCUGGGACUACGGGCGCGCGUCACCACGCCCGACUUAUUUUUUUAUUUUUAGUAGAGACGGGGUUUCUCCAAGUUGCCCAGGCCGGUCUCAAACUCCUGGCCUCAAGUGAUCCCGCCUCGGCCUCCCAAAGUGAGUGCUGAGAUUACAGACGUGAGCCACCGUGCCUGGCCCUUUUUUUUUUUUUUUUUUUGGAGCGUCACUUUGUUGCCCAGGCUGGACUAUAGUGACACGAUCAUAGCUCACUACAGCUUCAAACUCCUGGGCUCAAGUCAUCUUCCUGGCUUAGCCUCCUGAGUAGCUGGAACUACAGCCAAGGCCGCCGCGAUGCCGCACUUCCUGGACUGGUUCGUGCCGGUCUACUUGGUCAUCUCGGUCCUCAUUCUGGUGGGCUUCGGCGCCUGCAUCUACUACUUCGAGCCGGGCCUGCAGGAGGCGCACAAGUGGCGCAUGCAGCGCCCCCUGGUGGACCGCGACCUCCGCAAGACGCUAAUGGUGCGCGACAACCUGGCCUUCGGCGGCCCGGAGGUCUGAGCCGACUUGCAAAGGGGAUAGGCGGGCGGCACCGGGCGCCCUCCCCCAGCCCGCCCCGCCCGCCCAGCCCGGAGACCCCCAAGGCAGAGGGAGGCCGGCCUGUUGGCCCUCCACGCUAUCCCUCUGCAGCCUGGGCCCUCCCGACAGAGGCCCCAGGUGCGCUGGCAGUGGAGGUGGGGCACUUAGGUGCCUGGCUGGCCCAGGGCUUGCUCUCCGUGUCAAGCCGACUCACCCAGAGCCCACCCUCCCAAGCUCAGGGGCAUCCUCCGCUGGGCCCCAGUGCCUUUGCGCUGCGCAGCACUCUGCCCUCCACUGGACUCAGGCAUGUCUAUGGCUGCCUGUCCUGAGGCUCCGGAGCCCUCAUUUCUUCGUGAAGUCCCCAGCUCCCCUGCCUCCACUCAAUGGCACCGGCCCUGCAACUUUAGGCAGGUCGAAGCCAACCCAAGGAAAGAACCUAAGAACCUCGUUUGGAGGGAUGUCAGCUUGGGCCAGACCAGCCGCACCCCGCGGGGCUCAGGCUUGGAACUGGUGAGGGUGUGUGGUGGGGGUAUGCAGAGGGAUAAGACCGUGGUAGAGGAGAGGGUUGGUGAGGAGAGAGAGAGAGAGAGAGAGAGAGUCUGGGGGGAGCGGGCAAGCAUGGGGAGAUGAGAUGUGUAUAUGUGAGAGAGAGUGUGGGGGCCCCAGGCAGGGCAGGAGGUGGUGGAAACGGGGUGAACUCCGUGGGCUGUGUGAGGACUGUCCAUAGUGGGUCCCAACCCCCUCCCUCUGCUGGAGUUUCCUAGCCCUUCCCCCUCCCCAAGACUGUGGCAGCAGGCAGGAGCCCCUGCCCUCCCUCCCUGUCCUGUGCCACACUUCUGGGGCCAAACCCAGCCCCCUUGAGCCAGGCCCUGCCAGACUCCAAGCCCACCCUAGAACCCUCCUCCUGUGUGGAGACUCUGUUGCCCCACUUUGGACACAGAUUGGCAACCUGCCUCACCCCGCCCCCCUUCGCUGGGGCUUCCAUCUUAAUUUAUUCUCAAUAAUAAAGACUUCAUGAUGAUCUCUGCA